UAGGACACCCUGAAUGUCCGGUUACGGAAAUGAGACAGUUCCCAACUUGCUGAUUAGCUUGGGAAAGCAUUCCAGCGUCCCUGUUCCCAGCGUCUUUGAUUCCGGAUCACUGUACCAAAACACUUGGAGGGCCAAGGUUUUUACCCUCUCAAGAGGACAUUGUGCCUGUGGCUGUUAUUGUGUAUUUGAAGAAACAAAACGGCCCCUCAGUUGAAAAUAAAUGACUUAAGUUACAAGUGCCUCAAGUUACAUCAAGGCCACGAGAAUGACACACAUAACUUAUUGUUAAACUUUGGGGUAGAUAGAUUGAUGUACAGCUAUAUAUUUUGUCCUUUCUUUCACCUCAUGAUCUGUGUCAGUUGGGAAGUACAAAUCAUUAUUGGAAUGAAACUGUAAGAGAUCCAAUUCUGUGGAGAUACUUUUUGUUGAGGGAUCUUCCUUCUUGGUCUUCUGUUGACUGGAAGUCUCUUCCAGAUCUAGAAAUCUUAAAAAAGCCUAUAUCUGAGGUCACUGAUGGUGCAUUUUUUGACUACAUGGCAGUGUAAGUAUCUAGUUUUAUGAAUUAAAAAGAAGCUAUUAAAUUUUCCUGUAUUACUAGUCAAUAUCCAAGUUAAUCCUGACCCUGCUACUGAUUUGUUGCGUGGAUUUGGGGUCUAAUUGUUCUCGUCAAAACUGGGAGUUAAAUGACUUCCUUCAUAGGACCCUUUCAGCUUUAAUAUUUUAUUAUUUCCCUGUGGUGCCUAACCAGUAUUUGAAUAAUUAUAAGUAGUAUAGAUGGCAAGAAGUAAAAGACUUCUUAAAAGUCUCAUGAUCUUUAGAACAAUUGUCAUUUUGUUAAAUAAGUAAAUACUUUUCCGUAUUCAGAAAAAGGAUGAUCAGAGACCCCUGUUGUUUGGCAGGGAAGAAGAAAACCAUUCUAAAGGCUCUGAGAAAUAAGAUUAUAUUAGCACCGAAAAGCACUGACAUUUUUUAAUAUUGCGUAGGUGAGAUAAUUAAUGUUACUGAGCAACUGCAGUGUACUGGAUUCUACGAGGGAUGCUUUAUGUAUGUUUUACUCAUUUAAUCCUCAUGCAACAAGAAGGUGUUAUCUUUGUAUCCCAGAUGUGGAAUUAAGGUUCAUGGAGGUUAUGUGAUUUGCCUAAAGUCAUAUAGCUUGUAAGGGACUAUUCAGACUGGAACCCCAUUAUGCUACCUCAAAGAUAUAUAAUGACAUUAUAUAUCUGGAUAUAGCUUGUUUUUCUGAGAAACUCAAAUUUAACGCAUUAUUUUAAAAAUUUCAAAAUAUUUAUUCUUUAAAAAUUGUUGUGCUUGACUCAGUAGCAAAAUACAGAAUUUUUUUUUCAAAUUUUGAGUUAUUCAGAGCCUUUCCUUAUUCUAAUACAGAUGCCAUUAUGUCAAGUGUUGUGAGACUAUUUGAUUCAAAGGUGUGUUGUCUGUUAUAGAUAAUCUCAGCAAGUGCUGCUGUAUCUCACUUGCUAGGCAAUACCUGUACAAUAGCUAACCAUUGCAUCAAGUGUAUAUGAGGCUGUGGAAUUAGAUUUUGCCCAGGGAAUAGUAAUAAUAGUAACUACCAUUUAUGGUCAUAUAAAGUACUUAUCAUUUUUACAACCCUGAGUUAUUUCUUUCUUUUCUUUUUUUUUUUUUUGAGACGGAGUCUUGCUCUGUCGCCCAGGCUGGAGUGCAGUGGAGCGAUCUCGGCUCACUGCAAGCUCCGCCUCCUGGGUUCACGCCAUUCUCCUGCCUUAUCCUCCCGAGUAGCUGGGACUAGAGGCACCCGCCACCACGCCUGGCUAAUUUUUUGUAUUUUUAGUAGAGACGGGGUUUCACCGUGUUACCCAGGAUGGUCUUGAUCUCCUGACCUCGUGAUCCACCCACCUUGGCCUCCCAAAGUGCUGGGAUUACAGGCGUGAGCCACUGCGCCCGGCCAACCCUGAGUUAUUUCUGUUGCUCAAAUAAUACAGAUGAAGAAACUGAAAUUCAGACUCUAUAGAAUGUGCUGUCCAUACACAAGAAGAGCUUCAAAAUCCAGCCGUCCUAUGUAUGGAGCUGUCACUUCUUUUUUACACUCCCUGAUCAUUCAGAAUGAACCACGAUUUGCUAUGUUUGGACCAGGUUUGGAAGAAUUGAAUACCUCUUUGGUGUUGAGCUUGAUGUCUUCAGAGGAACUUUGCCCAACAGCUGGUUUGCCUCAGAGGCAGAUUGAUGGUAUUGGAUCAGGAGUCAAUUUUCAGUUGAACAACCAACAUAAAUUCAACAUUCUAAUCUUAUAUUCAACUACCAGAAAGGAAAGAGAUAGAGCAAGGGAAGAGCAUACAAGUGCAGUUAACAAGAUGUUCAGUCGACACAAUGAAGGUGAUGAUCAACAAGGAAGCCGGUACAGUGUGAUUCCACAGAUUCAAAAAGUGUGUGAAGUUGUAGAUGGGUUCAUCUAUGUUGCAAAUGCUGAAGCUCAUAAAAGACAUGAAUGGCAAGAUGAAUUUUCUCAUAUUAUGGCAAUGACAGAUCCAGCCUUUGGGUCUUCGGGAAGACCAUUGUUGGUUUUAUCUUGUAUUUCUCAAGGGGAUGUAAAAAGAAUGCCCUGUUUUUAUUUGGCUCAUGAGCUGCAUCUGAAUCUUCUAAAUCACCCAUGGCUGGUCCAGGAUACAGAGGCUGAAACUCUGACUGGUUUUUUGAAUGGCAUUGAGUGGAUUCUUGAAGAAGUGGAAUCUAAGCGUGCAAGAUGAUUCUCUUUUCAGAUCUUGGGAACUGAAACCAUUUGAAAUUUAUUACUAAGGUCGUGAUGUGAAUAUUUGCUCAGUCAGCCCACCUUGUCCUGCCUUUUUGCAGAUAGGCUUUCAUUUGGACAGCUAUAACUGCUGUGUUUUUUAUAUUAUUUUUACUCUUUACCAUAAAUCAAUUACAAGAAAAGAGUUUCAGUCCUAGUAUUUAGCCCCAAAAUGAACCUUUAAACAUUUUUUUGGUAAUUUUUAUAUUUUCUGUCUUUUUAAAAAUAUUAAAUUCUGGAAAAAACAAGUUUGUGCCUCUCAUUCCCUGAGUUUCUAUUCUUUUGGGUAUAAAGAUUGCCUUAGUGAGAAAUAGCAAAUUUGCUAAACUUUCUAUUCAGUCUUUUCAAGGGUUCAUAAGUGGUUAUCAGAAAAGAAAUUUUUAUCUAUUCUUAAUAAAUACACUGCUUAAAGACUGAAAAA